ACUGUAGUAGUAGCUGGAAAGAGAAAUCUGUGACUCCAAUUAGCCAGUUCCUGCAGACCUUGUGAGGACUAGAGGAAGAAUGCUCCUGGCUGUUUUGUACUGCCUGCUGUGGAGUUUCCAGACCUCCGCUGGCCAUUUCCCUAGAGCCUGUGUCUCCUCUAAGAACCUGAUGGAGAAGGAAUGCUGUCCACCGUGGAGCGGGGACAGGAGUCCCUGUGGCCAGCUUUCAGGCAGAGGUUCCUGUCAGAAUAUCCUUCUGUCCAAUGCACCACUUGGGCCUCAAUUUCCCUUCACAGGGGUGGAUGACCGGGAGUCGUGGCCUUCCGUCUUUUAUAAUAGGACCUGCCAGUGCUCUGGCAACUUCAUGGGAUUCAACUGUGGAAACUGCAAGUUUGGCUUUUGGGGACCAAACUGCACAGAGAGACGACUCUUGGUGAGAAGAAACAUCUUCGAUUUGAGUGCCCCAGAGAAGGACAAAUUUUUUGCCUACCUCACUUUAGCAAAGCAUACCAUCAGCUCAGACUAUGUCAUCCCCAUAGGGACCUAUGGCCAAAUGAAAAAUGGAUCAACACCCAUGUUUAACGACAUCAAUAUUUAUGACCUCUUUGUCUGGAUGCAUUAUUAUGUGUCAAUGGAUGCACUGCUUGGGGGAUCUGAAAUCUGGAGAGACAUUGAUUUUGCCCAUGAAGCACCAGCUUUUCUGCCUUGGCAUAGACUCUUCUUGUUGCGGUGGGAACAAGAAAUCCAGAAGCUGACAGGAGAUGAAAACUUCACUAUUCCAUAUUGGGACUGGCGGGAUGCAGAAAAGUGUGACAUUUGCACAGAUGAGUACAUGGGAGGUCAGCACCCCACAAAUCCUAACUUACUCAGCCCAGCAUCAUUCUUCUCCUCUUGGCAGAUUGUCUGUAGCCGAUUGGAGGAGUACAACAGCCAUCAGUCUUUAUGCAAUGGAACGCCCGAGGGACCUUUACGGCGUAAUCCUGGAAACCAUGACAAAUCCAGAACCCCAAGGCUCCCCUCUUCAGCUGAUGUAGAAUUUUGCCUGAGUUUGACCCAAUAUGAAUCUGGUUCCAUGGAUAAAGCUGCCAAUUUCAGCUUUAGAAAUACACUGGAAGGAUUUGCUAGUCCACUUACUGGGAUAGCGGAUGCCUCUCAAAGCAGCAUGCACAAUGCCUUGCACAUCUAUAUGAAUGGAACAAUGUCCCAGGUACAGGGAUCUGCCAACGAUCCUAUCUUCCUUCUUCACCAUGCAUUUGUUGACAGUAUUUUUGAGCAGUGGCUCCGAAGGCACCGUCCUCUUCAAGAAGUUUAUCCAGAAGCCAAUGCACCCAUUGGACAUAACCGGGAAUCCUACAUGGUUCCUUUUAUACCACUGUACAGAAAUGGUGAUUUCUUUAUUUCAUCCAAAGAUCUGGGCUAUGACUAUAGCUAUCUACAAGAUUCAGUGUCCCAAUGGAUACUUUUUACUACAAAGGCAACAAAAUUUCCUGGAUGAGCCAGGGGAGAAGAGGCUCAAUGAGUCAUAUUAGAAGCUUGAAGACCCAGACUCUUUUCAAGACUACAUUAAGUCCUAUUUGGAACAAGCGAGUCGGAUCUGGUCAUGGCUCCUUGGGGCGGCGAUGGUAGGGGCCGUCCUCACUGCCCUGCUGGCAGGGCUUGUGAGCUUGCUGUGUCGUCACAAGAGAAAGCAGCUUCCUGAAGAAAAGCAGCCACUCCUCAUGGAGAAAGAGGAUUACCACAGCUUGUAUCAGAGCCAUUUAUAAAAGGCUUAGGCAAUAGAGUAGGGCCAAAAAGCCUGACCUCACUCUAACUCAAAGUAAUGUCCAGGUUCCCAGAGAAUAUCUGCUGGUAUUUUUCUGUAAAGACCAUUUGCAAAAUUGUAACCUAAUACAAAGUGUAGCCUUCUUCCAACUCAGGUAGAACACACCUGUCUUUGUCUUGCUGUUUUCACUCAGCCCUUUUAACAUUUUCCCCUAAGCCCAUAUGUCUAAGGAAAGGAUGCUAUUUGGUAAUGAGGAACUGUUAUUUGUAUGUGAAUUAAAGUGCUCUUAUUUUAAAAAAUUGAAAUAAUUUUGAUUUUUGCCUUCUGAUUAUUUAAAGAUCUAUAUAUGUUUUAUUGGCCCCUUCUUUAUUUUAAUAAAACAGUGAGAAAUCUA